AGUCUGGGACGCGCCGCCGCCAUGAUCAUCCCUGUACGCUGCUUCACUUGUGGCAAGAUCGUCGGCAACAAGUGGGAGGCUUACCUGGGGCUGCUGCAGGCCGAGUACACCGAGGGGGAUGCGCUGGAUGCCCUGGGCCUGAAGCGCUACUGCUGCCGCCGGAUGCUGCUGGCCCACGUGGACCUGAUCGAGAAGCUGCUCAAUUAUGCACCCCUGGAGAAGUGACCACGCUGGAACCCACCCACCCGCUGUGCUGACCAUGGGCCCUGAGCGUCCUGCCCCGAAUUCACGAGGCUGAGGCAUCCGGGAGCUGGCGUAAUGCCUGGCCGCAGUGUGUGUGUAUCCGAUACCCCACUCUGGAAGGAACCAUCCAGUAAAGGUCUUUCAGAACCACUAAGGUCCCAGCCCUCACUAGGAUGUCAGGAGCCAGGUCUAGGCCCAGCUUUCACACUGUGGCAGCCCAGUGAAGCAGACUGGGCCAUGAACUCUCCUAGCCCUGGGGCCAGCCUGUUCCACAGGCACCCCUGCAGGAGGCGCUGCCAGGAGAGCCUUCCAUCUCGGGGCUCUUUGAGGUUCCCUCCUUCUGGGUGUUCUUCAGGCUGAGCAGAGAGGCUCCUGUACCCUCUCUCUCGGAAUCUGAAGAGCCAGAUUUAGGCCGGGCAAAGGGGCUCACCCCUAUAAUCCCAGGACUUUGGGAGGCCAAGGCAGGAGGAUCACUUGAGUCCAGAAAUUCAAGACCCGCCUGGGCAUCAUAAUGAGACCCCAUCUCUACAACAAAAUUUAAUAAAUUAGCUGGGCACAGUGUUCACACCUGUAGUCCCGGCCACUCGGGGCUGAGGCAGGAGGAUCACUGGAACCUGGGAGGUUGCCACUGCA